ACCUCCCUGGCCUUAGCUGACCUGUUUAUUCAAUGGGGUCCUAACAUUGCUGCUCAGAGUGGUAAAGAUAAUGAGAAGUGUAUGUGAAAGUGCCCUAAAUGGGGAGAGGGAGAAUUCUUAGGGCACCCUAGAUGGGAGACCAAGAGGGCAGUUUGAAGUCUGAGCGAGUUAGAGACGUGGCAUUUCCACUUAGUAACUGUGUGGCCCUGGGCAAGUUAAUUUCUCUGAGUCUUCUUUUCCUUAUCUGUGAAAUGAGGUAAUAGACUACUGUGGAAAUCAGUGAGACUGGGUAUGUCAAGUAGCUUGGCACAUAGUAAGUGCUCAACCAGCUAUUAUGAGGCGUCCAGGGUAGGAGGGCAAGACUUCCAGGAGGAGAUGACUUUGGGACAGGUAAGGUGUAGGUGUGUAGAGUGCCAGCUCAUAUGGGUAGUCCUACUGCAAUGCCAACCCCCAACCCCGGUUUUACUUCUCCAUUCUGCUCAGAGCAAGGGAGGUACUUCUACAAGUAGUCCUGGGAAACUCUUUGAGGUCAACCCCUUGUAGAUAGCUGGGGUCAUGGUCUCAUUUUCUACCUGGGCUUCGUUGACCCUUCCAGAAGAAAAAAGGCAUCUUUGUGUCCUUUGGGAAGUGCUUAAAGCAGUAAUAACUAUUUACAAGCAUAUGAUUAAGAAGCACUUUACCAGGCAUAUUAUUUCAUUUAAUCUUUAUGUAGACUUUGCCAGGUGCCUGGUGAUGUCAUCCUCAUUUUGCCGAUGAGGAAACUGAGGUUCAGAAAAGUAAAGGGAAGGACCUGCUUAAGAAUCCUUUUUUUUUUUUUUUUUUUUGAGACAGAGUCUUAGUCUGUUGCCCAGGCUGGAGUGCAGUGGCGCGAUCUCAGCUCACUGCAACCUCCGCCUCGUGUGUUCAAGCGAUUCUCCUGCCUCAGCCUCCCGAGUAGCUGGGACUACAGAUGUUCACCACCUCGUCCACUAAUUUUUGUAGUUUUAGUAGAGACAAGGUUUCACCAUGUUGGCCUGGCUGGUCUCGAACUCCUGGCCUCAAGUGAUAUACCUGCCUCGGCCUCCCAAAGUGCUAGGAUUACAUGCGUGAGCCACCACACCCAGUCAUUGCCUAAGAAUCUUGUAUCUAUUAAGUGAUGGAAGUGGACGUGUUUCUAGGUAAAUCCUGUAUUUUAUCCCCCAUUCACUGUUGCCUCUGAUUUUGCAACAGUUGCUAUUAUAAGGCCACAGGGGUAUUCUUUUGUUACUUUUAACUGGCUAGAAGUUAAAAGGCAAGGAAACAAGAUCUCAGGUAAAGCUUUAUUUAAAUAGAUACCACCCAAAGUGAGGAUCUCAGAAAAUAGUUGGAAUCUUUUUUUUUUUUUUUGAGACGGAGUUUUGCUGUUGUUGCCCAGGCUGGAGUGCAAUGGUGCCAUCUCAGCUCACUGCAACCUCCGCCUCCCUGGUUCAAGCAGUUCUCCUGCCUCAGCCUCCCAAGUAGCUGGGAUUACAGGCAUGUGCCACCAUGCCCGGCUAAUUUUGUAUUUUUAGUAGAGAUGGGGUUUCUCCAUGUUGGUCAGGCUGGUCUCAAACUCCCGACCUCAGGUGAUCGCCUGCCUUGGCCUCCCAAAGGACUGGGAUUACAGGCAUGAGCCACUGUGCCCAGCCUGAGAGCUGGAAUCUUUAAAAGAGGGCUUCUCUGUCCCUCAUUCCCUCCUCAUUAAAAUGAGGGGACUAGGCUAGAUUAUACUGAAGGCCCUUUCAGUGCUGUUAUGCAGUUGUGGUUAAAAGCUUGCAAUCAGACUACCUGGACUAAAAUCUUGGCUCUGCCACUUCCAAGCUGUGUGCUACUGAGCAAAGAGGUGCUACUUUACCUCUGAAAUGAUGCUCAGUACCUCUGAAAUGAUGAGAGGACUUUUUGGUAAGGGGCUCUGUGAGGAAGAAUUAUUCAUAGUUCAUUUUGAACCCCUUGGUGGUAUAGUUUCCUCAUCUGUAAAAUGGGGAUAGUAAUAGGCCUUAUUACCUGUGGCCUUAUUAUCAUGUAUGGCUGUUCUGAGGAUUUAUUUGAACUUAAUAUAUGUGAAGUGCCCAGCAUAUUUGGUAAACAUUAGCUAUCGUUAUUUGGGUUUAACGUGGUGCUUGUGCUGUAUUUUCCGUGUAUGGUUGGUGAAAGAAUAAAUUAAAGUAUGUGAUAAUACCAGGUCCGUCAACCAUAAUGUCAUUGCAAGCAUGAAACAGUAGCCAUCAUGGCAUUAUAUAAAUGUUGAUAUUUUUAUACAGUUGGCCCCAGGAACCUGUAAUCAUGUGCCACAAUGGGUUGCAAAGAAAGGUAAAGCUGUCCAGGCAUGGUGGCUCACGGCUGUAAUCCCAGCACUUUGGGAGGCCAAGACGGGUGGAUCACGAGGUCAGGAGAUCGAGACCAUCCUGGCUAGCACAGUGAAACCCCAUCUCUACUAAAAGAAAAAAAAAAUUAGCUGGGCAUGGUGGCGGGCGCCUGUAGUCCCAGCUACUCGGGAGGCUGAGGCAGGAGAAUGGCGUGAACCGGGGAGGUGGAACUUGCAGUGAGCCAAGAUUGCGCCACUGCACUCCAGCCUGGGCGACAGAGCAAGACUCCGUCUCAAAAAAAAAAAAAAAAAAAAAAAAAAGAAAGAAAGAUGAAAGCUGAUGGUAGGACGUUAGGUUUAGUAGCUCAACAUCCAAUUCAGUAAAUAUUUGCUAAAUCCCCUUAUGCUAGGCACAUGGAGGAUGUGGAGGUCAAUCCCAUCUCCAUAUCCUUCGAGGAACUCAGAGCUUAAUUUGCAAAUUACUGCAUUUGACAUCUUUAAAUGAAUUCAUAUCUUAUGUUUGCCUUGGCUGCAGAGUGAAGCCACUGAUUCUAAUCUGUUUUGUUGUGUCCCUAGACUUCUGUUAGGUGCCUGGAUUAGAAACCUCAGAUUGCUUCCUAAGCCUUUUCAUCCAUUAAUUCGCAAGUCCCUGAGAAAGACCCCGUCUUAUGUAACAGAGAGUAGCAAUACUUGACAAUAACAAUAAGGUGCCUAAUGGCUUACAAAAAUGCCUACACUUGCUUACACAUGCUUUUACUCAUUUAAUCUUAUCUGUGUCCCUUCAAGGAAGGUAAGGUGCAGAUUAGGAUCUCUGUUUUAUAGUCGAGGAAUCUGAAUGGAAGCCAAGAAGCCAUGAUGCUAUUGAGUGGCCCAUUUCACGUUGAAAUCCAGUCUUCUGUCUUCAAAUUCAGUGUACUUACCACUAUCCUGCCCGGAUUGUAUUUAUUCAGUAUUUCCUGAGCACCUAGAAUGUGUCAGUUCUGUUUUAGCCUGGAGAUAUCAUGGUAGAAAGGUACAGAGUCCCUUGCUCUCAUGCAGCUUAUAUUCUACUGGCAGCAAACAGAAAAAUACAGCAGUAAAUGAACAAGGGAAUUUGGAUGAGGAAUAAGUGCUGGGGUGAAAUCCCAUCUCUAUUAAAAAUACAAAACUUAGCUGGGUGUGGUGGCACGUGCCUGUAGUCCCAGCUAUUCAGGAGGCUGAGGCACAAGAAUUGCUUGAACCUGGGAAGCAGAGGCUGCAGUAAGCCGAGGUUGCGCCAUUGCACUCCAGCCUGGGCAACAGAGCGAGACUCCAUCUCAAAAAGAAAAAAAACCCAACAAACAAAAAGAAAAAGAAAAGGCCUUGCUAGGAUGGUGACGUUUUUGCUGAGAUUUGCUCCCAGGGACGGGCCAGCCAUUUGAAGACAUGUCAGAAGGAAGAGCAAGGGUAAAGGCUGUGAGGUGGCAACAAGCUUGGACCGUAGCAUCCUGAGACAUUUUGAAUUGACACUUCUCAAGAUUUGACUGGAUCAGAGUUCAUCAUGUCAAAGUUGAAAAGCUCAGAGUCAGUCAGGGUGGUGGUUCGCUGUCGGCCCAUGAAUGGCAAGGAAAAGGCUGCUUCGUAUGACAAAGUGGUGGAUGUGGAUGUUAAGCUGGGGCAGGUGUCUGUGAAGAACCCCAAAGGGACGGCCCAUGAAAUGCCCAAGACCUUCACCUUUGAUGCCGUCUAUGACUGGAAUGCCAAGCAGUUUGAACUGUACGAUGAGACGUUCCGACCACUUGUUGACUCUGUCCUGCAAGGUUUCAAUGGAACCAUUUUUGCCUAUGGACAAACUGGGACAGGAAAAACCUACACCAUGGAAGGAAUCCGUGGUGACCCUGAAAAAAGAGGAGUCAUUCCUAACUCAUUUGACCAUAUCUUCACCCACAUCUCUCGAUCCCAGAAUCAACAAUACCUGGUCAGGGCUUCUUACUUAGAGAUCUACCAGGAGGAGAUCCGAGAUUUGCUCUCAAAGGAUCAGACCAAAAGGCUUGAGCUCAAAGAGAGGCCUGACACAGGAGUGUAUGUGAAAGACCUGUCUUCCUUUGUCACCAAGAGUGUGAAGGAGAUAGAGCAUGUGAUGAAUGUGGGGAACCAGAACCGUUCUGUCGGUGCUACCAACAUGAACGAGCACAGCUCGCGUUCUCAUGCAAUUUUCGUUAUCACUAUUGAGUGCAGCGAGGUGGGCCUCGAUGGUGAAAACCACAUCCGUGUAGGAAAAUUGAACCUUGUAGAUCUUGCUGGCAGCGAACGGCAAGCCAAGACCGGCGCACAAGGGGAGAGAUUAAAAGAAGCUACCAAGAUCAACCUCUCCCUUUCCGCUUUGGGUAAUGUCAUCUCUGCUCUAGUGGACGGCAAAAGCACUCACAUUCCAUAUCGGGACUCAAAGCUUACCAGGCUCCUCCAAGAUUCCCUUGGUGGCAAUGCCAAGACUGUGAUGGUGGCCAACGUGGGGCCUGCCUCUUACAACGUAGAAGAGACUCUGACCACUCUGCGAUAUGCCAACCGUGCCAAAAACAUUAAGAACAAACCAAGGGUCAAUGAGGACCCCAAGGAUGCCCUCCUUCGAGAAUUCCAGGAAGAGAUUGCUCGGCUCAAGGCCCAGCUGGAAAAACGGUCCAUUGGUAGGAGGAAGAGGCGAGAGAAGCGGAGGGAAGGUGGUGGCAGUGGUGGGGGUGGGGAAGAGGAGGAGGAGGAGGGAGAAGAGGGUGAGGAGGAAGGGGAUGAUAAGGAUGAUUACUGGCGGGAACAGCAAGAAAAACUGGAGAUUGAGAAGCGGGCCAUUGUAGAGGAUCACAGCUUGGUUGCAGAGGAGAAGAUGAGGCUGCUGAAGGAGAAAGAGAAAAAGAUGGAGGACCUGCGGCGGGAGAAGGAUGCUGCCGAGAUGCUGGGCGCCAAGAUCAAGGCCAUGGAGAGUAAGUUGCUUGUUGGAGGAAAAAAUAUAGUAGAUCAUACGAAUGAACAGCAGAAAAUCCUGGAGCAGAAACGACAGGAAAUUGCAGAGCAGAAACGUCGAGAAAGAGAAAUCCAGCAACAGAUGGAAAGUCGAGAUGAGGAGACCUUGGAACUUAAAGAGACAUACAGCUCAUUGCAGCAAGAGGUGGACAUCAAGACCAAAAAACUCAAAAAGCUCUUCUCCAAGCUUCAGGCAGUGAAGGCUGAGAUCCAUGACCUCCAAGAAGAACACAUCAAGGAGCGCCAAGAGCUAGAGCAGACUCAGAAUGAGCUCACCAGGGAGCUGAAACUCAAGCAUCUUAUUAUAGAAAACUUUAUCCCUCUGGAAGAAAAAAGUAAAAUUAUGAAUAGAGCCUUCUUUGAUGAAGAGGAAGAUCAUUGGAAACUACAUCCUAUAACCAGACUGGAGAACCAGCAGAUGAUGAAGCGGCCAGUCUCAGCCGUGGGAUAUAAGAGACCAUUGAGCCAGCACGCAAGAAUGUCCAUGAUGAUUCGUCCAGAGGCCCGAUAUAGGGCAGAAAACAUUGUGCUGUUAGAGCUGGACAUGCCCAGCCGGACCACCAGAGACUAUGAGGGUCCAGCCAUUGCCCCCAAGGUCCAGGCUGCAUUGGAUGCGGCUCUGCAGGAUGAAGAUGAGAUACAGGUGGAUGCAUCAUCAUUUGAAAGCACUGCAAAUAAGAAAUCCAAGGCCAGGCCUAAAAGUGGAAGGAAGUCGGGAUCCUCCUCCUCUUCCUCAGGAACCCCUGCAUCUCAGCUUUAUCCACAGUCUCGGGGGCUGGUUCCAAAGUAAAGCCAGCUUCUCCUCUCCCAGGGCGGAAACAGCAUUUGCCUUCUGAGAGAAGAGACUAGCAAAAAGCUGCAGAGAGGAUUCGGCCCAAACUCAGAACUGUUCCCCUGAGGAGAAGCGGUGGCCUCUUUGCAGAUCAACCAACUUAAUCUGGUUGAACGUGCUGUUCCUAAUCUGGCACUCAGCCCCUCUGGGAAACAUCUUUUAAUUAGCAUCUCAGAAAUGCAUGGGUAAGGUAAAGUGCGAUAGUUCAAGUGGAAAGCAAGAGAAUGACCAGUGACCUUGCUUCCUUCCCCCUUGCCUUCUUCUCCCCCUUCCCCUGUGCUCCCUUUCUCUCCUCUCUCCUUUUCUAGCCUGUUCUUUACAUGGGGCUCCCUUCUUGUUGAACAAUAGGGCAGAAUCAGGAGUCACCUUAGCAGGACCACAUCUUUGGAGCCUCGGGAUAAAAUGACAGUGAGGUUGAAAAGUGAAAACCCUAGAACUUGAAUAGGUGCCUGUUCUUGUAGGGAGAAAUGAGAAAUCGCAUUUGGAUCCAGGCCCCAGGUGGGCACCAUCAGCAGUCUUGCUUCCAUGCACCUCAGUAAGAAGUGGAUCUGCCUUUGGGACCUGCUCAGUGAGGAAAUCUCUUCCAAUUUCUGCUUCUGAAUGAUUCAAUGUUGGGAGCAAUAGAAAUAACAUUCCCUUUGCCUUCUCUGAGUGUUUAGGGAAAUAGCUUCUUUAAAACCUCAAAACCAUGACCAUCCUGUCAAAGACCUAAGUCUGUAAGCUGGUGCCAUGUCCAUACACCAUGUCACUUUACUCUUCAUUUGUCACCAUCUUUUCCCAUGCACGCAUACUCUGAACAUCCUUGUGUGGGCCCAUCCUCUGCAUCCAGAGCAUGCUCUGCAGUGGGCCUGUUUUGUGGAAGAAAGGAGGCUGUCUCUGCCUUCUCUGAUGGGACUGGAGUUGAGGGAAGGAGCUGUAUUGUGGCACUUCUGAAUUCCCCGUUUUGUUCCAUAUUGGUAUAGAGAGCAGAAGAGUAGCUAGGCAGAUGCAGAGAUGGAGACAUGAGACUCAGUGCAGUGGGCAGGGAAGACAUAACAGAUGGAAGCAAAGGAAUCCUGCCUGCCUUCAGCAGAGAAUUCACCGAAUCCUAGAACUGUGGCUCCCUCCAGGCAGAGCCUAAGAUGCUGGUGAAGAAUAGCUGUGUGAUUGAAUAGGCUCAAAGGAGAGUUCAGAAUUCCCAUUUACAUAUUACUAGUUUGGUUUGUAAGUUUUAGUUCCUUGUAUUAUUGAGAUUCAGAGCUUCAUUUUAUGUUGGUCAUUAGGUGAAUAUUACUCAUUUUCCCUCAAGAGAAGCUCAUAAGUGUGUGUGGGUGUGAGAGCACGAUGGUGCCUGUGUUCUGUGAAUGUGUCCAUAUGUGUCUGUAAGAGAGACAGAGACCAAGAACUUGCCCAAUUUUAGAAAUACACUAAUGUGCAGUUGUUGCCUUUUGUCUGUAUUGAAGGCCCAUUGAAUGACUAAUCCAGGCUGGAAGCAUUCCCAUGUGGGUGUCUGAGUCCAUGAGCCAAGCCUGAGGGGACAGUGAGUCUCCAGGUCUGCCACACUGGUGCACCUUGCUGGCACGGUGCCUCAGGAAGGUGGCGACUCAGGUGGGCCUUGAGUUAUAUUUUAACUCAGCUGCUCAGUUCCCAGGGCACAUUUCUGGAUCAGAACCCAUGGGAAACAGGAGGUACUAAGUGCAAUGUCUUAGCAUUCUGCAAAAUGGAGAUCUGUUGUCCAGCGGCUUAUCUCCUUUUUAGUAACCCUUCUUUCUGAACCCAGGGCCCUUUUCAGCCUUCCCUCAUAUUUUCUUGAGAUCAAACUUUACUUCUUUCUUAUUUACUAAGAAUUUGCCUGUUUGAAUAAGAACAAAACGCUAAGGUGGGUAGCCUAAGCUGAUUUUCUGCUGGUUACACGUGUCUCUCACACCACAUUUCCUCAAAGCUAAUCUGAAUUCUGUAGGCUAAAAAUAUUCAUGUAGCAAAUCUGAGAAUUGAAAACUGCAGAUAACCGGCCGGGUAUGGUGACUCAUGCCUGUAAUCCUAGCACUUUGGGAGGCCGAGGUGGGUGGACCACCUGAGGUUAGGACUUCAAGACCAGCCUGGCCAACAUGGUGAAACCCCAUCUGUACUAAAAAUACAAAAAUUUGCCUGGUGUGGUGGUGCAUGCCUCUAGUCCUAGCUACUCGGGAGGCUGAGGCACGAGAAUCACUUGAACCUGGGAGGCGGAGGUUGCAGUGAGUCGAGAUAACACUACUGCAUUCCAGCCUGGGUGACAGAGUGAGACUCCCCCUCAAAAAAAAAAAAAAAAAAAAAAAAAACAGAAAGAAAGAAAAAGAAAACUGCAGAUAACCCUAUACAUUAAUACUGGUAUCUCGAGGUGACUCUUCUGACCAAGGGUGGUUAAGUGACACAUAGAACUUUUCUAAGAGAAGACAGACAAGUUGACAGGCAUGCCUUGUACUCAGCUGUGUUCAUGUGGUGGUCUGUGGAAAGAAAAGAAGACUCAUUUGGAAAUGAAGCUGUCCCUUUCCAAGCAGUCUCUGGUGCUUUUCUUCUCUCAAAAUGGAUCCGAUAAAUAUUUGAAUAGAGCAGAUUGUAGAAUGUCGUGCUGUCACCAGAAAGCUGCUGUUUUGGGUUCUGCAUUGAGCCAAAUAUGUAGAGGACCUACCAAGCCCACUGAGGGACUAGGUUUUCAUGUCUCUAGUCAUACCUAGAAUGUUCUGAGCCGUCUGAGGGCCUUCAUGCCGGCAGCAGCUAGCAAAGCCAGAAAGCAAGUCUAACAGGAUCUAAGAUGACCAUCAGGAGAAGGAGUUUGAGACUGUGUAUGCAACCCCCAAUAGACCCCCUUUUACUCUGAUCUGGAGAAUGUAUCUGGCUUCAUAUUUUCAAGUCACAUGUCUCUCAGACCCCUGGAUUCAGAACCCAAGGCCACAAAUCAUAGGCAUGAAGCACUUUCUUAAGACUGACCUAACGCUGGAUUAUUUCCCGUCCAAUGCCUGCAUGCUGCUUGAAUUGCUCCACCCACACCUCCAUGACCAAGGGCGCCAGAGUGCUGCAACUGGGGCGUGGGCCGCUCUCUGCUUUUCCUGUCUGACUCUGACAAGUCCUCCCUCACUGAAUGUAGAAUCGUUGCCAAGUUUCUGAGAAGUGUCGAUUCCCUGUUAACAUGGAUAUCAGUUCUGCCUCACAUUUCCCACUUGAGGUUGAGGCGUACUGGAGACAACACCUCAGACCAUCUGAACCCCAUCAGUGGACGAAAAUGGGGCUGUUAAUAUACUCUAAAAGCCAUACUAAAAAUGCUCUGAGGGAACUGGCUAAGAAUAGUGGGCCUGGUGAUUGUCUAUCACGCAAGGCUUUGUUUUGUACUGUUCAGAAAUCUGUCACCUUUCUGCCUGCCCUUGUUUCCUGAAUGAAAUGCUUCUGGGGUUAUUUAUGAAAGGAGUGAUCCUGGGGCAGGCAGGAGGCAGUGGGCUUCAUGGCUCCUUGAAGUUAUUACUGAUCUUGACCUUCUCUUUGGCUACCUUUAGACAAAGAAUACGCCAAUCAAUACUUGGGGCUCUAAGUUUUACAAUUGAUAUUUAUUUGUAUCAUCUCUUUGUCUAGGAAUGUAAAAGUGAUUCUAAACUAAGAUGUGUAAUAAAAAUCAAUCAGAUUUAUUGUACCUACAAAAA